AGCUCGCGGUGUUGUUCACUCGCGCGUCGAGCACACGGUGGGUCCGGCGGCGGGUUGGCGCCCCAGGCGGCGUUCCCUGUGGCCUGGCGCCUGGGCCGCUGCCCUGAGCGGGUUCCGCCCCAGAGCCCGACCCUCCUGGGGGCUCUAGGCGGAGUCCCGCGAGCCGAGGGGGACCGGCGACCGCUGCCGAAGCAUGAAGAAGGGGUAAGGCGUGAGCCCCCAAGAUUUCACGCAUGCCCCCUAGCUUCGGUACUCUGACACCUUCUCUUGCACUUGCGGAUGAUGAACUGGAAUAACGAUGAAAGAAAGCACAUCCGAUCUCAACAUUCACGUCCUGCCCUAUAACCGAUUAAUUAAUUGAUCCCCAGCUAGACUAGUGUUGGAGAAAUCAGCAUGUUAAAACAACUGUUGAUGAUAGCUGUUGGAGUAAAGUUGCAGUGGAAGCUAUGGCUGCAAAAUCGUUAAAAUCUUCAAGGUGAACUGGCACAAAGGUUAAUCUCAAGAUGCCGCUAGUGAAAAGAAACAUCGAUCCUAGGCACUUGUGCCACACAGCACUGCCUAGAGGCAUUAAGAAUGAACUGGAAUGUGUAACCAAUAUUUCCUUGGCAAAUAUAAUUAGACAACUAAGUAGCCUAAGUAAAUAUGCUGAAGAUAUAUUUGGAGAAUUAUUCAAUGAAGCACAUAGUUUUUCCUUCAGAGUCAACUCAUUGCAAGAACGUGUGGACCGUUUAUCUGUUAGUGUUACACAGCUUGAUCCAAAGGAAGAAGAAUUGUCUUUGCAAGAUAUAACAAUGAGGAAAGCUUUCCGAAGUUCUACAAUUCAAGACCAGCAGCUUUUCGAUCGCAAGACUUUGCCUAUUCCAUUACAGGAGACGUACGAUGUUUGUGAACAGCCUCCACCUCUCAAUAUACUCACUCCUUAUAGAGAUGAUGGUAAAGAAGGUCUGAAGUUUUAUACCAAUCCUUCGUAUUUCUUUGAUCUAUGGAAAGAAAAAAUGUUGCAAGAUACAGAGGAUAAGAGGAAGGAAAAGAGGAAGCAGAAGCAGAAAAAUCUAGAUCGUCCUCAUGAACCAGAAAAAGUGCCAAGAGCACCUCAUGACAGGCGGCGAGAAUGGCAGAAGCUGGCCCAAGGUCCAGAGCUGGCUGAAGAUGAUGCUAAUCUCUUACAUAAGCAUAUUGAAGUUGCUAAUGGCCCAGCCUCUCAUUUUGAAACAAGACCUCAGACAUACGUGGAUCAUAUGGAUGGAUCUUACUCACUUUCUGCCUUGCCAUUUAGUCAGAUGAGUGAGCUUCUGACUAGAGCUGAGGAAAGGGUAUUAGUCAGACCACAUGAACCACCUCCACCUCCACCAAUGCAUGGAGCAGGAGAUGCAAAACCGAUACCCACCUGUAUCAGUUCUGCUACAGGUUUGAUAGAAAAUCGCCCUCAGUCACCAGCUACAGGCAGAACACCUGUGUUUGUGAGCCCCACUCCCCCACCUCCUCCACCACCUCUUCCAUCUGCCUUGUCAACUUCCUCAUUAAGAGCUUCAAUGACUUCAACUCCUCCCCCUCCAGUACCUCCCCCACCUCCACCUCCAGCCACUGCUUUGCAAGCUCCAGCAGUACCACCACCUCCAGCUCCUCUUCAGAUUGCCCCUGGAGUUCUUCACCCAGCUCCUCCUCCAAUUGCACCUCCUCUAGUACAGCCCUCUCCACCAGUAGCUAGAGCUGCCCCAGUAUGUGAGACUGUACCAGUUCAUCCACUCCCACAAGGUGAAGUUCAGGGGCUGCCUCCACCCCCACCACCGCCUCCUCUGCCUCCACCUGGCAUUCGACCAUCAUCACCUGUCACAGUUACAGCUCUUGCUCAUCCUCCCUCUGGGCUACAUCCAACUCCAUCUACUGCCCCAGGUCCCCAUGUUCCAUUAAUGCCUCCAUCUCCUCCAUCACAAGUUAUACCUGCUUCUGAGCCAAAGCGCCAUCCAUCAACCCUACCUGUAAUCAGUGAUGCCAGGAGUGUGCUACUGGAAGCAAUACGAAAAGGUAUUCAGCUACGCAAAGUAGAAGAGCAGCGUGAACAGGAAGCUAAGCAUGAACGCAUUGAAAACGAUGUUGCCACCAUCCUGUCUCGCCGUAUUGCUGUUGAAUAUAGUGAUUCGGAAGAUGAUUCAGAAUUUGAUGAAGUAGAUUGGUUGGAGUAAGAAAAAUGCAUUGAUAAAUAUUACAAAACUGAAUGCAAAUGUCCUUUGUGGUGCUUGUUCCUUGAAAAUGUUUGGUCAUUCUAGUGUUUUGCUUUCUUUUCCUUAUAAUAAAUGACCCUUUUCCUCCAUAACUUUUGAUUUCUAAGGAAAAUAUUAGCAUACAUUUCAAACUAAAUGUUUUACAGUGGCUUAUCUUUUUUUUCCCCCUGAAAAGACUAAUUUGGUCAAAUAAACCACUAAGUAUUAAGCAUGGACAGCUGUUGUUAGAGUAGCAGAUUCAGUUUUUUGAUAUAUCUUAAUUGUGUACUUUGUGAAUUUUAAUUUAAAGAAAGCAACUGAAAUUGAAAUCUUGAGGGCAGCUGUGUCUACUAAUGAGCCUUAUUCCAUUUCCUGAUGUUUUAAAAGAAGAAACACUGCCUUGAUUAUACGAAUACACUCAGAAAGUACAUUUAGCUUGUAGUGUUGAAUUCUCUUAAAGGAAUGCUUGAAUUUUUUCAUUAUUGUUUUAUUGUUUUUAUAUACUUGCCUUAUUUGAAUGUUUAGCAGUAUCCCCUUCCCACUUAUAUAUUGUGUGAUAUGAUUUUGCUUGCCUAUAGGAGUUAAAAACUUUUCCAUGUGAAAUACUCUGACUUAAACAUACAUGUAACUUACAUAACUGUUAAGAAUAACAGUCUGAUUUAAUAAAUGGUUCAUUUUAAAAGUU